AGAGCCCGGGCGGCUACGGAAGCGGUGAGACUGUCUCUCGGCUGCAGCCCUGGUGCGACCCGGCCCGUUGCCGUAGAGAUGGGCAGGGCUGGAUGGAGUGGGGUGCGGUGAGCUGAGCUGACCCUGCUUCGCCACGGGGACUGCAGUGACCCCGGCUUGCCGGCAGGGCGGGUAACAGGUUGAGCCAGGGUGGGGCUGCUCAGGGGCGUGGAGCCGAGGCCAGGAUUUCUCUGAAGACCCGGCACAGGCUAUUCCUUUCUGCGACGAGCCCAUUGCUAUGGAAACCAAAGCGUUAGGCCAGCGGGGAUUGAGGCUGCGGGAUCAUGACGGGUCUCUCUCCCGAAGAACCUUGCCUAAGGCUUCCCCAAGCGGCUACUUCCUGAGCGAACCCGCCCACCCGCCUGAAGGAGAGAGAGCCCUGCAUUUUAACUUCCCUAUCAGAAGCGAGAAAAAUAGUUAUCAUUUUGAGAGGGCUUACUCUAUGCCAAGCCCUGAGAAAACUCUUUACGUGGAUUAUCUCGUUUAAUUUCACAACAUCCUUUUAAGCUUUGUUUAAGACUGAGAAAGUGAGGGUCCGAGAGUCUAAUGAAUGCUCUGGGCACCCAGGCCGCACCUGAGGAGCACCGACGACUGCACGGUCUGCGGCGCGGGAAGCAGAUCUGCGGCUGAACCUCUACCCCAAUUACUUAGCGGCGACUGAGCCUAUCGAGCAGUUUUCCAUGGACACAGCCUAGCAGAAAGACGCAGCCUUCGUGCUUCGCUGACUGCUGACCACUGACCCACCGCCUUGAUGACAGCACCCUCGUGUGCCUUCCCAGUUCAGUUCCGGCAGCCCUCAGUCAGCGGCCUCUCGCAGAUAACCAAAAGCCUGUAUAUCAGCAAUGGUGUGGCCGCCAACAACAAGCUCAUGCUGUCUAGCAACCAGAUCACCAUGGUCAUCAAUGUCUCAGUGGAGGUAGUGAACACCUUGUAUGAGGAUAUCCAGUACAUGCAGGUACCUGUGGCUGACUCCCCUAACUCACGUCUCUGUGACUUCUUUGACCCUAUUGCUGACCAUAUCCACAGCGUGGAGAUGAAGCAGGGCCGUACUUUGCUGCACUGUGCUGCUGGUGUGAGCCGCUCAGCUGCCCUGUGCCUCGCCUACCUCAUGAAGUACCACGCCAUGUCCCUGCUGGACGCCCACACGUGGACCAAGUCAUGCCGGCCCAUCAUCCGACCCAACAGCGGCUUUUGGGAGCAGCUCAUCCACUAUGAGUUCCAAUUGUUUGGCAAGAACACUGUGCACAUGGUCAGUUCCCCAGUGGGAAUGAUCCCUGACAUCUAUGAGAAGGAAGUCCGUUUGAUGAUUCCACUGUGAGCCAUCCCACGAGCCCCUGCAUUGGAGUCAGAGAUUAAACUAAUUGUGAGAUGGUGAAGAUAAAUUUUCUGCCCUGUGAGUGACACUGGCCAGGGGAUAGGUUGAGGCAGAUGGUGCCCAGAAGAAAGAGGGCAGCACCCAUUGCACAUGGCAGGCCUGGAAUCCUGCAGCCCUCCCCAAAAACAGAUUGACCCAGGAAUGAAUCUGCUACAAUUCCACCUCAUUCUUUCACACCCAGAGCCAGAGCCUUAAGCAUCAUGGUACCUCUUGCGCUUCUUACAGUGAGUGCCAAUCUACUAGAUAAAUGGCCUUCAGGCAGUGCUCCAGGAAUCCUGGGGGGUCCCAGGCCACCUCUGCUUCCACCUUCACUAUAAGUGGCCCAGUUCUGGUUUUCUAGAUUGUACUUAUGCAUAAGAUAGUUUUUAAAGAAAGCAUUCCACUGUGUAAAUUUUUUUUUGUCUUUUUUUGAAACUGUCCUGCUCUGUCACCCAUCCUAGAGUGCAGUAGUGUGAUCAUGGCUCACUGUAGCCACAACCUCUCAGGCUCAAGUGAUCCUCUUACCUUAGCCUCCUGCGUGGCUGGGACUACAGAUGUUUGCCACCAUGCCCGCCUCAUUUUUUUUCUUUUUUUAUAGAGAUGAGAUUUUACUAUGUCGCCCAGACUGGUCUCAAACUCCUGGCCUCAAGCAAUCCUCACGCCUCAGCCUCCCAAAGUGUUGAUGAGCCACUGUACCCCGAUACCACUGUAUAAAAAAUUUAAAAAAAAUUGUGAGUGCUAUUGUACAUGGCAAAGUUUCAAAGAGCUCUUGGCCAUCCCUCACCAAACUUUGGCAAAAGAUGGUGUUAGUCCCCUUCUCCAGGGCACAUGAGAAAAACAGGCCUAACAUCAGGUCUCAGCGGUUCCUCUCACAGGCCUUGGCUUGGAAGGCUGGAGCUUCGGACCAAGGCCCAGCCCUGUCACCUCCUCUUCAUGUGAUGUGGACCCCUGGGAGCAUCAGUGUCCUCAUCUGUCCAAUGACAGCCCUUUUCUCACAGAGUUAUUGUGAAGAUUCAACAAUUUCUUGGCAUAGUGCCUGGCACAUGGUGUGUGCUUAGCGCAAAUGGCAGCUCUCAUCAUGAAUGAUAGACUCUUUCACCCUGCUGGUCCCAGGUCGGCACACACAUCCCCAUAAUGGCAUUUCUCCUUUCUGUGCACAGCACUUUAUUGUUACAAAGUACUCUUCCAAAAAGUUACCCUGUGUGUAAAAAAAAAAAAAAAAAAAAAUGGUUUAAGUCCUUUCAGACCCUACCUCACAGGAGGCCUAGACUUAGAGCCUUUUGAGAGCUUCCGUCUUGUUUAAUCUAGGUGCAAUCUAGAGGUCCUGAAACAAGGAGCACAGUUCCAGCUUCCCCCAAUCACUUCUAAACAGUGACUGCAGCCUUGUUUAGAAUCACUAUGAAAACCUGCACCCCGGCUGACUACUGGGAUCCAUAAGGGGGCCGUGUCAAAGGGACUAACUAGUGGACUCCAUCAGUAGGCCCUGGAAUUCAGGAUUGUUCACAUCCUCUUGGUGCCAAGGACCUGGCUGAAGACCAGCUCUUCUGAUCCAGAGGUUUUCAGCAAACAGCAUUUGAAACAAAAGCACAGCUGCUCUGUUUGACACCAAACUGUGGCUCCAGAUUCCAGUAGAAGCCAAAUGCUUUUUCUUUUAACAGCUGGGUGCCUGUAAUCCCAGUUACUUGGGAGGCUGAGGCAGGAGAAUUGCUUGAACCCAGGAGGCGGAGGUUGCAGUGAGCCGAGCUUGCACCAUUGCACUCCAGCCUGGGCAACAAGAGUGAGACUCCAUCUCAAAAAGAAAAAAAAAAAAAAAGAAAAAGAAAAGAAAAAAAGAAAUGCUUGGGACCAGAAAUAUUUUGGAUUAUUUUCAGGUUAAUAUUUGCUUUACCUGAAGCAAAUAUUACUUGAGCAUCCCAACUCUAAAAUCCAGAAUGCUUAAAUGAGUAUUUCCUUUGAUAGUCAUUUCAGCUCUCAAAAAGUUUUAGAUUUUGAGCAUUUCACAUUUUUGGAUUUGAGAUCCAUGAAUGGGUCUCAAACUAUAUUUCACUUGGCGGGGGGGUGGCUAUUGUAGAUUUUUUUUCCAAUUGCUCAUUAUUAGUAUAUAGAAAUACAAUUGAGGCCGGGCGUGGUGGCUCAUGCCUGUAAUCCCAACACUUUGGGAGGCCGAGGUGGCCAGAUCACUUGAGGUCAAGUGUUCGAGACCAGCCUGGCCAACAUGGCAAAAGCCUUGUCUCUGCUAAAAAUACGAAAGCAGGGCGUAGUGGCAAGUGCCUGUAAUCCCAGCUACUGAGAUUAGAGAAUGAAACAGGAGAAUUACUUGAACCCGGGAGGCAGAGGUUGCAGUGAGCCAAGAUCAGGACAUUGCACUCCAGCCUGGGCAACAGAGCAAGACUCCAUCUCAAAAAAAAAAAAAAAAUUGUUCUAUGCCUUCUGGCCUCCAUGGUUUUUUCUCAGAAAUCCAGAGGCAUUCUAACUAUUGUUUCCCAACAGGUAAUGCUUUAUUUUUCCCCAGCUGCUUUUUAAGAUUUUCUCCUUGUCUUUGGUUCUCAUCAGUUUAAUUAUGAUGUAUAUGGACAUGGAUUUCUUUCGGUUAUCCUUAUCAGAGUUCACAGAGCCACUUGAUUGUGUUUCAGAUAUCUGGGAAGUUCUCAGCUAUGAUUUCUUCAAGUAUUGUUUUCUGUACCAUACUGUCCUGUACUUCUGUGUCAUUGAUAACAUGAAUGUUAGAGCUUUUGACAUUG